AGAGACCAGCAGAACGGCAUCCCAGCCACGACGGCCACUUUGCUCUGUCUGCUCUCCGCCACGGCCCUGCUCUGUUCCCUGGGACACCCCCGCCCCCACCUCCUCAGGCUGCCUGAUCUGCCCAGCUUUCCAGCUUUCCUCUGGAUUCCGGCCUCUGGUCAUCCCUCCCCACCCUCUCUCCAAGGCCCUCUCCUGGUCUCCCUUCUUCUAGAACCCCUUCCUCCACCUCCCUCUCUGCAGAACUUCUCCUUUACCCCCCACCCCCCACCACUGCCCCCUUUCCUUUUCUGACCUCCUUUUGGAGGGCUCAGCGCUGCCCAGACCAUAGGAGAGAUGUGGGAGGCUCAGUUCCUGGGCUUGCUGUUUCUGCAGCCGCUUUGGGUGGCUCCAGUGAAGCCUCUCCAGCCAGGGGCUGAGGUCCCGGUGGUGUGGGCCCAGGAGGGGGCUCCUGCCCAGCUCCCCUGCAGCCCCACAAUCCCCCUCCAGGAUCUCAGCCUUCUGCGAAGAGCAGGGGUCACUUGGCAGCAUCAGCCAGACAGUGGCCCGCCCGCUGCCGCCCCCGGCCAUCCCCUGGCCCCCGGCCCUCACCCGGCGGCGCCCUCCUCCUGGGGGCCCAGGCCCCGCCGCUACACGGUGCUGAGCGUGGGUCCCGGAGGCCUGCGCAGCGGGAGGCUGCCCCUGCAGCCCCGCGUCCAGCUGGAUGAGCGCGGCCGGCAGCGCGGGGACUUCUCGCUAUGGCUGCGCCCAGCCCGGCGCGCGGACGCCGGCGAGUACCGCGCCGCGGUGCACCUCAGGGACCGCGCCCUCUCCUGCCGCCUCCGUCUGCGCCUGGGCCAGGCCUCGAUGACUGCCAGCCCCCCAGGAUCUCUCAGAGCCUCCGACUGGGUCAUUUUGAACUGCUCCUUCAGCCGCCCUGACCGCCCAGCCUCUGUGCAUUGGUUCCGGAACCGGGGCCAGGGCCGAGUCCCUGUCCGGGAGUCCCCCCAUCACCACUUAGCGGAAAGCUUCCUCUUCCUGCCCCAAGUCAGCCCCAUGGACUCUGGGCCCUGGGGCUGCAUCCUCACCUACAGAGAUGGCUUCAACGUCUCCAUCAUGUAUAACCUCACUGUUCUGGGUCUGGAGCCCCCAACUCCCUUGACAGUGUACGCUGGAGCAGGUUCCAGGGUGGGGCUGCCCUGCCGCCUGCCUGCUGGUGUGGGGACCCGGUCUUUCCUCACUGCCAAGUGGACUCCUCCUGGGGGAGGCCCUGACCUCCUGGUGACUGGAGACAAUGGCGACUUUACCCUUCGACUAGAGGAUGUGAGCCAGGCCCAGGCUGGGACCUACACCUGCCAUAUCCAUCUGCAGGAACAGCAGCUCAAUGCCACUGUCACAUUGGCAAUCAUCACAGUGACUCCCAAAUCCUUUGGGUCACCUGGAUCCCUGGGGAAGCUGCUUUGUGAGGUGACUCCAGUAUCUGGACAAGAACGCUUUGUGUGGAGCUCUCUGGACACCCCAUCCCAGAGGAGUUUCUCAGGACCUUGGCUGGAGGCACAGGAGGCCCAGCUCCUUUCCCAGCCUUGGCAAUGCCAGCUGUACCAGGGGGAGAGGCUUCUUGGAGCAGCAGUGUACUUCACAGAGCUGUCUAGCCCAGGUGCCCAACGCUCUGGGAGAGCCCCAGGUGCCCUCCCAGCAGGCCACCUCCUGCUGUUUCUCAUCCUUGGUGUCCUUUCUCUGCUCCUUUUGGUGACUGGAGCCUUUGGCUUUCACCUUUGGAGAAGACAGGUGAGCCAGGGACAUGGCAACCCCGCCCCCCAGCAGCUCCCGCUCUUCCAUCCUCAGAGUGCUGAUGGCACCCCUUCCUCAGGAAGUGGCGACCAAGACGAUUUUCUGCCUUAGAGCAAGGGAUUCACCCUCCGCAGGCUCAGAGCAAGAUAGAGGAGCUGGAGCAAGAACCGGAGCCGGAGCCGGAGCCGGAACCGGAGCCCGAGCCCGAGCCCGAGCCGGAGCAGCUCUGACCUGGAGCUGAGGCAGCCAGCAGAUCUCAGCAGCCCAGUCCAAAUAAACUCCCUGUCAGCAGCAA